AGAGCAGAGUCUGCGAUCUUCCCAGCACAGACGUUUGGACAGAGCAGGCUCCUAAGGUCUCCAGAAUGCCCGUGCCAGCCUCCUGGCCCCACCUUCCUAGUCCUUUCCUGCUGAUGACGCUACUGCUGGGGAGACUCACAGGAGUGGCAGGUGAGGACGAGCUACAGGUGAUUCAGCCUGAAAAGUCCGUAUCAGUUGCAGCUGGAGAGUCGGCCACUCUGCGCUGUGCUAUGACGUCCCUGAUCCCUGUGGGGCCCAUCAUGUGGUUUAGAGGAGCUGGAGCAGGCCGGGAAUUAAUCUACAAUCAGAAAGAAGGCCACUUCCCACGGGUAACAACUGUUUCAGAACUCACAAAGAGAAACAACCUGGACUUUUCCAUCAGCAUCAGUAACAUCACCCCAGCAGACGCCGGCACCUACUACUGUGUGAAGUUCCGGAAAGGGAGCCCUGACGACGUGGAGUUUAAGUCUGGAGCAGGCACUGAGCUGUCUGUGCGCGCCAAACCCUCUGCCCCCGUGGUAUCGGGCCCUGCGGUGAGGGCCACACCUGAGCACACAGUGAGCUUCACCUGCGAGUCCCAUGGCUUCUCUCCCAGAGACAUCACCCUGAAAUGGUUCAAAAAUGGGAAUGAGCUCUCAGACUUCCAGACCAACGUGGACCCCGCAGGAGACAGUGUGUCCUACAGCAUCCACAGCACAGCCAGGGUGGUGCUGACCCGUGGGGACGUUCACUCUCAAGUCAUCUGCGAGAUAGCCCACAUCACCUUGCAGGGGGACCCUCUUCGUGGGACUGCCAACUUGUCUGAGGCCAUCCGAGUUCCACCCACCUUGGAGGUUACUCAACAGCCCAUGAGGGCAGAGAACCAGGCAAACGUCACCUGCCAGGUGAGCAAUUUCUACCCCCGGGGACUACAGCUGACCUGGUUGGAGAAUGGAAAUGUGUCCCGGACAGAAACAGCUUCGACCCUCAUAGAGAACAAGGAUGGCACCUACAACUGGAUGAGCUGGCUCCUGGUGAACACCUGUGCCCACAGGGACGAUGUGGUGCUCACCUGUCAGGUGGAGCAUGAUGGGCAGCAAGCAGUCAGCAAAAGCUAUGCCCUGGAGAUCUCAGCGCACCAGAAGGAGCACGGCUCAGAUAUCACCCAUGAAGCAGCGCUGGCUCCUACUGCUCCACUCCUCGUAGCUCUCCUCCUGGGCCCCAAGCUGCUACUGGUGGUUGGUGUCUCUGCCAUCUACAUCUGCUGGAAACAGAAGGCCUGACUGACCCUCAGUCUCUGCUGCCUCCUCCUUUCUUGAGAAGCUCAGCCUGAGAGAAGGAGCUGGCGAGAACCUUCCCCACACUCAGCUCCAAACGCCUCCUCUCCCAGGUCAUCUGCCUGCCCACACGCUCCUGUUCCACCUUCACAAGACCAUGAUGCCCCAAAGCAGUGUCUCUAUUCACGGUCCUGAGCAGGGGCCAUGGGAUUGGGCUCUGGGCACUGACUCAUGGCACCUCCCUAGAAGGUGAGAAACACUCCAAAUCUAAACACACCAGGACUUCUCCCAUCCGUCGCCUUGGGACUGGCCAUAAACCACAGACUCUCUCCAGGCUCUCAAGAGUUAUCCUGUCUUCUGGAUUCCUGCCUACCCCAACUCCCCCAGCCUUGUUGAGGUUCUCUACUGCCUCCUGAAUACACAUGAACCCCUAUACCAAUUUUAAGAAAAAAAUGAUUCUCUUUCCUCUUUGUCCAAGCAUCCUAUCCCUCAAACCCAAAAAGAAAGAAGCUCUCCCUUCUCUCUCUGUGAUGGAGACAGUAUUUCUUCUAGUAUCCUGCAGCCUUCCCAGUCCUGCUGCUUGUGGUAGAAAUGCUGCCACAGCCCAACAUUGAGGAGCCCUCGAUGACUGCCCUUUACAACUCAUAUUCAGUUCUGCCUCCAAAAUGCAUGUGUCCACUUACAUGAGAUGGUAAAUGUUUAACAAUGGACUUUCUGAAAGGGAAAAACCAAAAGCUGUUUUGCAGUGCUUGCCAAUUUCUCUAGUGUAAUAACUCCCAACCUGACCAAUUUCACACUGCCAACAGUUAAACAACCAGAUUGCAAGAUUCCUGAAAUUUAACAAUUGGUUUUCAGGGCCCAGUCCAAGCCUGCUGCUGGAAACCUCAGAGUUAAAUCCCUAUUCUCCACACCUCUCACCUCCACCACCCCUCCCUGUCCCAGCCAGCAUCAUCUCUUUGGGGACCACUCCUCUGGCUUUCAUUUUUCAGCCACAGUGAUUCUUUGGAAAAGUCAAAUCAUAUCACUUCUCUGCUUCUUCCCCAACACAGCUGCAUGGCUCCCGCUCUCCCUCCUUCAAGUCUCUGCUCAAUGUCACUUCAUUAAAGGCACCUUCUAUAAACUACCUUGUAUAAAAUAUUAUUUAUUUUCUCUAUCCCGGCAUUCUAAUUUCUCUUAUCCUAAUUAAUUUUUCUUUAGCCCUUAUUUUGAUGAGUAUUAUGCCGAAUACAGGCAGCCCUCACUUUUCAUGGCAGUGCAAGAUUGCAAAAAUGACUGUGCAACCUGAAACCCAGGAAAGCAGUCUCCAUAGUCAAUCAGAAAAACAAUGAUCAUUCUGUGACCUUUACCAUUUUUUGUCAAAAUAUUAGAAACUCUCACACUCUCAGUUACAAAUGUAGAGGACAAUGAAAAUAUAAUGAAAUAAAUAUUUAUUUGUGCACUACAAUUCAAAGCAUUAGAAACAUUGAGAGUUCAAGUGCUGUUUCUUUGUAAAAAUGUAUCCAGAGUAGUUGGAAGAGUGCUUGCCUUUUUUUGUAUAUUUCUAAUAUGGAGUGAUAUAGUUUGGCUCUGUGUCUCCAUCCAAAUCUCAUCUUAAAUUGUAAUCUGCAUGUGUUGUGGGAUGGGCCUGGUAGGAGGUGACUGAAUCAUGGGGGCGGACUUCCCCCUUGCUGUUCUUGUGAUAGUGAGUUCUCAUAAGAUCUCAGUGAGUUCUCAUGAGAUCUGGUUUUUUGAAAGUGUGUGGCAAGUCCCCCUUCGCUCUCUCUCUCUCUCUCCCUCCUGCCACCAUGUGAAGAAGGUGCCUGCUUCCUUUUCUCCUUCCACCAUGGUUGUAAGUUUCCUGAGGCCUCCCAGUCAUGCUUCCUGUUAAGCCUGUGGAACUGUGAGUCCAAUUAAACCUCUUUUAUUCAUAAAAUAUCCAGUUUCUGGUAGUUCUUUAUAGCAGUGUGAGAAUGGGCUAAUACACGGAGCAAGCAUUGUUUCUUUUCAUUUGUUUAUUUUAUUUUUAUUUUUUUGAGAUGGAGUUUCACCCUUAUUGCCCAGGCUGGAGUGCAAUGUCGUGAUCUUGGCUCACUGCAACCCCCGCCUCCAGGGUUCAAGUGAUUCUCCUGCCUCAGCCUCCUGAGUAGCUGGGAUUACAGGCAUGUACCACCACACCCAGCUAAUUUUGUAUUUUUAGUAGAGAUGGGGUUUCUCCAUGUUGAUCAGACUAGUCUUGAACUCCCGACCUCAGGUGAUCCACCUGUCUUGGCCUCCCAAAGUGCUGGGAUUACAGGCAUGAGCCACCAUGCCUAGCCAGCAAGCAUCAUUUCUAUUAUACCUUGGUGUUUUGCCAUCUUUCUAAGUUUGGACUAGCUUCCAACAUCUUAUCCCUUGAAUUUUCAAUAUUGUGGAAUCACUCCAGAAGAUCCUUUCAUGUGAAGUUUUUUGCUGGCAUUUCAACCUUUGGGACAUCUUCAGCCCUUUUAUUACCACUCCUCUCCCAUUUGUGGCAGUUUGCGUUUACUACCUCCCUCUGGCUGCCUAUCUGAAGUUCCUGCAUCAGGGUCUACAUUGCCACAGUCAACUAUUUGUACUUCUAGAAUUCCACUCACAUUCAAUUUGAACCUCACUUGCAGCAUUUUCACUUCUCAUUUCUUCACUGCACUUUCAUCUUGGUUGCAAAAUUCCUCUUUCAAUUAUUCAUUUCUGUAAAAUGUCAUAUGGGCUCAUCACUGGGAGGCAAGGAGGCAACCCAACUAUAGGAUUUGCUGUUUGAGUAGGAGAGCCAUAGGGACCAAUCACCAACAGACUUUGAAAGACACAACAUGACUGGUUACUGAUCAUGACGAGCUUUUAUUACCAUGGUGAUUUGUGGACUGAAGAGCUAGCCCAGAAGUUUGUACUCUAUGCAAAUUACAUUAAAUUUACUAUGGCACCUAAAUUUUGAGACUUGUGUUGUGGGACUGAUGUUACUUAACUAAACUAUGGUAAGAGAAAUGCAUGCAUGUCAUCACCAAAGUGAGAACUGCCUGUAUUUAUCUAUGUUACGCAAAUGGAAUGUCAGUUAUAUCGUGGGGGGUUGGGGGUGGGGGAGGAUUAUCUGUAUCCUCAGUUGCCAGAACUGUGUCUGCCAUAUAAUAGGCUGUCAAUUUUUUUAAAUGAGUGAAUACAUCAUUGAGGUCAUUGGUUUCUACUAGGUGUUGGAUUUCAAAAGAAAACUUCUCUUCAUUUGAUCACUUGGCUUGUGUGCUGUAUUCUCAAGCUCUUUCUUUAAAGACUACUCUCUCUUCUUUCUGUUUAAAACAUUCCAUCAAAAAUUCAACAUCCUCUAGAAAGUAAGAAAGUGCUAACAAGAAAAAAAAGUCAACCCCAAAACCAAAACCCACAGUGACUGGAGUACAUCAAAGAGGCGCAGGAACCAACUGAAAGAGCUCCCAAAGGCCAAAGCUGGAACACUUUCAGCAAAAAAAUAAGUAAAGUAGUAAUGAGUUAUAGUCCAAAGUAUAAAAUAAAUAUCUGAGUCCAUACUGAUAUAAAUAAAUGAUUGAAUAAAUUAAUGGGAAAGAAGAGAAGAAUCUCCAGUGCAGAAGAGUCCCAGAUAAUUUAUUUAUACACUCCACUCUAAAGGAGGUGGAACAUAACUUCCACUCCUGAAGUGUGGGCUGUGCACUGCGACUUCUUUGCAAAGAGUACAGCAUGGAAAAAAGGAGAAAAAAUAACUUUACAGUGGAAAAAUCUGACAAAUACAGCUUCAGCCAGGUGAUCAAGAGUUCAUCAACAGUUAUAAAUCAACAUCAAGAAUCAUAAAUCAUGUCACUAAUAUGUACCUUUAAUAUGAUGUGAUGAAGAUGACACUUUUCCUCUAUUACCUUCCCCCCAAAACUCACAACCCCAAUCUAAUCAUGAGGAAAACAUCAGACAAAUUUCAAUAAGGAGGCAUUCUGCAACAUCGGGCCCAGAACUCCUCAAAACUGUCAAGGUCAUCAAAAUCAAGGAAAGUCUAAAAAACUGUCAUAGCCAAGAGAAGCUUGAGGAGAUAUGACAAGUAAAUGUAACAGGUAUCCUGGAUGGGAUGCUGGAAGAGAAAAACGACAUUAGGUAAAAAGAAAAGAUCUAAAUAAACUAUGAACUUUGAUUAAUCA